ACCCUCUAGGCUAGGCUGAGCGGCGGAGGUGGCCGUGCCGCUGGAAGCGGACAGACCCGAGUUAGAGGUGGGGGCGGGGGUCCAUCGCCCGCGGCCGGGCCGGCGCUCCCCUCCUACCCUCCCCGCGACCCCCGUCUGGCCCCCACGGCUAACGGUAGCGCAGCCGAACACGGCCCACGGGCAGGGCGCCGAAGAGGAGCAGGCGCGCGCCCGGGGACGAGCAGGGCGCAGUGAGGGAGGGGCGCGUCCACUGCCCCGGCCGGCCGACCGACACCGACCCCGCCUACUGCGGCGCGGGGACCCUUGGCAAGACUCGUGGCUGUGACCCAUGGGCCUCUGAGGAGGCGUUGUAAGUCCGCCCAGCUCCCCACUUGCUGUGCUCUCACUCAAUGCGAAGGGAACCAAGGUACCAGGGCCAAGUGGGUCCAGACAUCCACACGGAUUCUGAAAGGGCAGGUCAAGCAGACUUUGUCCAGCCAUCAGCCACGGCCUCUCGACAGCACCAAGAUGGAAGUCAAAGGUCAGCUGAUCAGCUCUCCUACCUUCAAUGCCCCAGCUGCCCUGUUCGGAGAGGCUGCCCCCCAGGUGAAGUCAGAGCGUCUGCGGGGGCUGCUUGACCGGCAGCGGACCCUGCAGGAGGCCCUGAGCCUGAAACUUCAGGAGCUCCGCAAAGUGUGUCUCCAGGAGGCGGAGCUGACUGGCCAGCUGCCCCCUGAGUGCCCACUAGAGCCUGGUGAACGGCCCCAGUUGGUCCGCCGGCGGCCCCCCACAGCCCGCGCCUACCCUCCACCGCACCCCAACCAAGCACACCACUCCUUGUGCCCUGCUGAGGAGCUGGCUCUUGAGGCCCUGGAACGCGAGGUGUCAGUGCAACAGCAGAUCGCGGCGGCCGCCCGCCGCCUGGCCUUGGCCCCUGAUCUGAGCACCGAGCAGCGCCGGCGCCGGCGCCAGGUCCAGGCAGAUGCACUGAGGAGGCUGCAUGAGCUAGAGGAGCAGCUCAGGGAUGUCCGGGCCCGCCUUGGCCUCCCAGUGCUCCCGCUGCCCCAGCCACUGCCACUGUCCACGGGGUCAGUGAUCACCACCCAGGGAGUCUGCCUGGGCAUGCGUCUUGCUCAGCUCAGCCAAGAGGACGUAGUUCUGCACUCAGAGAGCAGCUCCCUCUCAGAGUCUGGGGCCAGCCAUGACAACGAGGAGCCCCAUGGCUGCUUCUCUCUGGCCGAGCGCCCCUCACCACCCAAGGCUUGGGACCAGCUGCGGGCAGUAUCUGGGGGGAGCCCUGAGCGGCGAACCCCAUGGAAACCACCUCCAUCAGAUCUUUAUGGGGAUCUGAAGAGCCGGCGGAACUCUGUGGCCAGCCCCACCAGCCCCACACGCUCGCUGCCCAGGAGUGCCUCCAGUUUUGAGGGGCGAAGUGUGCCUGCCACCCCUGUCCUCACCCGGGGCGCUGGCCCCCAGCUCUGCAAACCUGAAGGCCUUCAUUCUCGUCAGUGGUCCGGCAGCCAGGACUCCCAGAUGGGCUUCCCCCGGGCGGACCCUGCCUCCGAUCGCGCCUCCCUCUUCGUAGCUCGCACCCGCCGCAGCAACAGUUCUGAGGCCCUGCUGGUGGACCGGGCCGCUGGUGGGGGAGCUGGCUCCCCGCCUGCCCCUCUGGCUCCCUCUGCCUCUGGCCCCCCAGUCUGCAAGAGCAGUGAGGUGCUGUAUGAGCGCCCCCAACCAACCCCUGCCUUCUCCUCCCGCACAGCAGGCCCCCCAGACCCUCCCCGGGCCGCCCGGCCUAGCUCAGCUGCCCCUGCCUCCCGAGGUGCCCCCCGGCUCCCACCUGUGUGUGGAGACUUCCUCUUGGACUAUUCCUUGGACCGGGGCCUGCCCCGCAGUGGCGGUGGAACAGGCUGGGGGGAGCUGCCGCCUGCAGCUGAGGUCCCAGGACCCCUCUCCCGCCGGGAUGGGCUCCUCACCAUGCUCCCCGGCCCACCACCUGUGUAUGCAGCUGACAGCAACAGCCCCCUCCUCCGCACCAAGGACCCCCACACCCGUGCCACCCGCACUAAGCCCUGUGGCCUGCCCCCAGAGGCUGCCGAAGGCCCUGAGGUGCAUCCAAACCCUCUGCUGUGGAUGCCCCCACCCACCCGUAUCCCCUCGGCUGGUGAACGCAGUGGCCACAAGAACCUGGCUCUGGAGGGGCUGCGGGACUGGUACAUCCGGAACUCGGGACUGGCUGCGGGGCCCCAGCGCCGGCCUGUGCUCCCUUCCGUGGGCCCGCCACACCCACCCUUCCUCCAUGCCCGCUGCUAUGAGGUGGGCCAGGCGCUGUACGGGGCCCCCAGCCAGGCGCCACUCCCACACUCGAGGAGUUUCACGGCGCCCCCUGUCUCUGGCAGGUAUGGGGGGUGCUUUUACUGAUGGGUAGGGGUCUCGUAAGGCAGAUGGCGAAGAUAUCCAGGCCAGGGAGUGGCUAGUCAUGAUAGCUAAUGAAUUGGACCAUGAGGAAACUAGCUGCUGUGAUGGCACAGGGUCACUCUACUGCACAUGACCUGCAUUAGUCCAUGGGGUCCUGGUGGAGGGGAUCUUGGGCACUGGUAGCAGCAAUUCUUUAUCAAGUUAUAGGCUGAAGAUGAGCCUUGAAGCCAGGGUGCCGGGAGGAAGGGACAUCUCAUGCCCCUUGCUGUUUUCUUCCUUUUUUCUCCAUGCCCCAGAGCCUGAAAGUGCUGUCCUGUGCCUGCCUCCACCUCUUUAACGAGCCUCUUUUCCUUUCUUUUUCUGUGUCUUGUCUGUCUUUUCUUCUUCUUGUCUUCCCCGCCCUGUCCUCCGGAUUCCUGCUACCCCUUCUAAAGAUACUACGCGGACUUCCUGUAUCCCCCGGAGCUGAGCGCUCGUUUAAGUGACCUGACGCUAGAGGGGGAGCAGUCCUCCAGUUCUGACACCCAGACCCCGGGGACACUGGUCUGACCCCUUCUGAUAUGUCCCUUGUUGGCCUGGGCACGAUUCCAAUCUGGGGAGCACACAGCUGACCUCGCUGGGCCCUGGGGUGUGGUUGCUCUCAGUCCUGAGCAGAGUGCGCCAACCUAAUCUUCCAAGGCCCCUGGCUCCCCGUAGGCCCAGGAAGGUGUCUGACACCCUGCUUCUUCUCUCACACUGUGCUGGGGACUGGGGGCCCUCAGCUAGCUUAAAAGAGGGGGGAUGAUGUCAUGGGGACCCCAAGCCCCUUCCUCCAUUUAUGUUUACAGUUGUGACUUAGGUAUUCACUGUCUUCCUCCAACACUAGGCGUUUUACAAAAGGGAAACUGUGAUCUCAUCUGGUUGGGUUCAUUCCUGUUCCCAUGCCCAACCAGGUUCCAUUCAGGAACCCCCUCCAUAAAAUGGACCAUAUCGGGUCUCAGGGCCAUUUAGGGCAGCCAGGAGACUCCGGUGUGAACAGAAAUCCCUGCCACGCAUCGCCAGGGCAGUUGGGGCAGUGGGCUCUCUGCCCACACUUGGAAGGACUGCAGUCUGGGUGGGAUGCCUGAAAGAGCCCAACCCCCUCUGUGCCCAUGGCCUCUGCCCUGACCACCCCCAGUCAGGAGGCCCCACAGGAGGGGCACCCGGUAGAUGCCAGUGAAAUCCUCAGGGGAGGUCUGCCUGAAAGAGCCCAACCCCCUCUGUGCCCAUGGCCUCUGCCCUGACCACCCCCAGUCAGGAGGCCCCACAGGAGGGGCACCCGGUAGAUGCCAGUGAAAUCCUCAGGUGAGGUCUGCCUACGGGCCACGGGCCACUCACCACUCACACCUUCCUUGGCUUUCCUUCCACCCUUUUUUUUUUCUCGAGACGGAGUCUUGCUCUGUCACCAGGCUGGAGUGCAGCGGCGCAAUCUCAGCUCACUGCAACCUCUGCCUCCUGGGUUCUCCUGCCUCACCCUCCCGAGUAGCUGGGAUUACAGGCACACGCCACCAUGCCCGGCUAAUUUUUGUAUUCUUAGUAGAGACAAGGUUUCACCAUAUUGGCCAGGCUGGUCUUGAACUCUUGACCUCGUGAUCUGCCCGCCUUGGCCUCCCAAAGUGCUGGGAUUACAGCCGUGAGCCACUGCACCCAGCCCCAAUCCACCACUUUUUAAGCAAACCCACACAAGUUGUGUUUUCUAUGAUACCUGUCUGUGAUUUUCGGAGCUGGGGGUUCCCCUACCCCCUUUUCCUGGCGUUAAGCUUUUCUUUUUAUACCAGUGGAUCUGGACCCAAGACAUUACCCACACUGGAAGGGGAUUUGUAUAAUAAAUGUGUAAACUGAA